AUAAAGUUUAUUUUGAAGAAAGAUAUUGUUUCUUUAGUCUCAAAACAAGAGACUAGGAAAGAUCCAAAACACAGAGCAGGAGUCCACAGGGGAACCUGCCCUGCCUCAGUAAAAAUACAGUGUUGUUGCUGUAGGAAGACUCCCGGAUUCUACCCCAGGAUACUUCAUGAGAACGAACCCCUUCAGAGAGGCCCUACAAAACAGAUUAGAGGGAAGACAGAGGGGUCCAAGGGAGAUGGUCUCUCUUCUCAAGUAGGAACACCCCAGCCUCAGACAGACACAGCAGGAAGGGGCCUGAGAGGCUGACAGAGGCAGGAUGGGUGCAAGGCAGGGGUGGAGGGGAGGGACCAGCCCGGGCUGCACCAGUGGGAGUGGCUCCACCCUUCCCACCUCAGAGCCAUGGGGAGCCAGGGCUCUGGCGGGGUGCCCUUGGUGCAGGCUCCCUACACAGUCCUGCUGCUGCCGCUGGGGACAAGCCGCCAAGACCCAGGGGCCCAGAGCUUCUUCCUUUGGCUACGCAGGAUGCAGGCUCUGGAGAGAGAACAGGAUGCCCUGUGGCAGGGUCUGGAGCUGCUACAGCAUGGCCAGGCCUGGUUUGAAGACCAUCUGAGGGAGGCACAGCGACAGCAGCUGCAUCUAGGGGCCCUUGGUGAGAAUUUUCUAACAGAUUUACACUCAGAGCCUGGUCGCCCCCCGUUAGCCCAGAUUCAAAAGGUGAACAUCUGUUUGCAGAAUCUGAUUCAUGAGAAGUUCUCCCCAAGUCCACUGAACAAGGCUAGUUCCUGCACCACCCAGGAUUCAAAGGAAAGACGAAGGGAGCAGAACUUGUGGCAGCAACAGGAGUUGUCAAGGCAGCAGAAAGGAGUCACCCAGCCAAAGGAGGAGAUGGCUCAGCGGGGCUGCACCAAGGGGCCAAGAGGCCCUACCCGUGUCUAAACCCUCCUCUCACUCCCCUAAGCCUGGUGAAAGAGUCAGAAGCCCCAGGCUCCUUUUUCUGUUUCUUAACUCAACAGCUAAAAAAUGGCUCCAGGUAGUGAGUCAAUGAAGUUCAGACAUGUUGGUGUAAAGUUUCUCCUCUGCUCCUGAAAACUUCAUCUUCUUGGUGUCUCAUGUCCUCAUUCUCCCCUAUAUGACAUGCAAAAACGAUCUUUCUUUGAAAUCCCUCUGGGAAGAAGACAUGUUUAUUGAAACUGUCCUUCAGCCUUAAAUACAAAAAUAAAACUGAAACUGCUCCAGAAAGCAGCUUUCUCCAAAAA